AGAGUCUGAGGACUAUCCAGGGCCUGACUGCCAGCUAGCCAGCCAUGGGCCAGGAUUAUUACUCUGUGCUCGGGAUCACUCGCAAUUCAGAGGAUGCCCAGAUCAAGCAGGCCCCUGAGAAUUAAGUGCCAUUAUUAUCCCACAAGUGCACUAGUAAAUGGUGGAGCCAGUGUUCAGAUAUCAGGCCUCCCAGAGUUGCCAGUCAUGGGCCUAUUCCUGGGCCAGGUCCUGUAGGGGAUCAGUGGCAUAAGUGGAGAGUCUGCGGUGUUGGAGAAAAAAGACACAAACUCAUGAAAGGAUCUGAGAACAAUUCAGGACAGUGUAUGAUGUCACCCACUCUUCGGAGCAUCUCAUUGACCAGAAGGACCCAUCCAGGGAAAGGUACCGCAGACUCGCCCUUAAGCACCACCCGUUGAAGUCAAAUGAGCCGUCUUCAGCAGAGAUUUUCAGGCAAAUAGCAGAGGCCUACGACGUGCUGAGUGACCAAUCUAGACACACAGAGAAGACAGAAUACGGACCCGCCUUUCUCAGUAGAAGCAAGCUGAGGUGGAGGACGUGGGGUGUGGAGCCCAGGAUUACACUGACUCGCUCAUCCUGGCAGGCAGUGUGGGAGCUGGGGCACAUUCCCCACGCAUCCCUAUGCCCUGCGGGGACGGGACCUUCCCCGGGAGAAACAGAGGAAACCAGCAGAGUGAAGAAAGUGUGAUCCCCGCCCCGGCACCCAGGGCCGUCCUGCGGGGCUUUCCCUGGGGGAUUGUCCUGGAGACUAAUCCUGGUUCCUGCGGAAGUGCAGCUAGAAGAUCACUAAGCCAUGAAGAGAGGCAUCUACGACAAGUUUGGAGAAGAGGGCCUGAAGGGUGGGAUUCCUUUGGAGUUUGGAUCCCAGACCCCAUGGACAACUGGUUACGUCUUCCAUGGCAAACCUGAAAAGGUGUUCCACGAGUUCUUUGGUGGAAACAACCCCUUCAGUGAGUUUUUUGAUGCAGAAGGAAGUGAGGUAGAUUUGAACUUUGGGGGGCUCCAGGGCCGAGGGGUCAAGAAGCAGGACCCCCAAGUCGAACGGGAUCUCUACCUGUCCCUGGAGGACUUAUUCUUUGGCUGCACCAAAAAAAUUAAGAUCUCCAGAAGGGUGCUGAACGAGGAUGGGUACUCCUCCACCAUCAAGGACAAGAUCCUGACCAUUGAUGUGAAGCCCGGUUGGAGGCAGGGCACACGCAUCACCUUUGAGAAGGAAGGGGACCAGGGCCCCAACAUCAUCCCAGCAGACAUCAUUUUCAUCGUAAAGGAGAAGCUACACCCUCGCUUCCGCAGGGAGAAUGACAACCUCUUCUUCGUGAACCCCAUCCCUCUUGGCAAGGCUCUCACCUGCUGCACUGUGGAGGUGAGGACCCUAGAUGACCGUCUGCUCAACAUCCCCAUCAAUGACAUCAUCCACCCCAAAUACUUCAAGAAGGUGCCAGGGGAGGGGAUGCCAUUGCCGGAGGACCCCACUAAGAAAGGGGAUCUCUUCAUCUUCUUCGACAUCCAGUUCCCCACCCGCCUCACACCCCAGAAGAAGCAGAUGCUGCGCCAGGCAUUGCUGACAUGACUGUGGUGGGCUGGAGCAGGGGUGAGAGGAGGCUAGCCGGGCCUCACCCCACCCCUACCCGCCACAGCCUCAGGGUGUGCAGGGGAGCCUGCUGCACAGAUAUGAUACAAGGGUGGGAUGGCGCAGGGCUUAAACUGACAUAAUAAAGAUCUAUUUCCUGUCCUCCA